CUGCGGCCUCCCAGAGGCUUGGUUGAGAGCUCUGGCUCUCACUCCCCCACCUCCACCCAGCACCUGCCCCGGUCCAGGCUCACCCCCUACCCCUCCACCUGGUCAGUGGUGGCUCGGCCUCCUCUCAGCCCCUCCACCCCUCCUGGCUGUACACACCCUCAAGCUAACGGAAUUCAAACUGGUGGAGGAAGGCCUGCCCUGUCCCUCCCAGCCCCUGCCUCUCCCUCCCUACUCCCAGCCUCACUGGACCACUUUCAAGUCCUCCAGUGCUCCAGGCUCCAUCUUCAUGCCUCCAGGCCUUUGCACGUGCUGGUCCCUCUCCCAUUCUCCUGGUUAACUCCUCCACCUCCAUCCGAGCUAGGAUCUUCCCCUGGAGAGUGUCCCGGUUAGCACUACCCCACAACACACACACACACCGACAUACACGCCCCACAUCACAGGGACCACAUCCCACACAGGCACAGACACACUGCAUGACGCAGAUCACAGGCACAAAGGUGCAUGCGUGCACACAUACACACUCCCACUCCAUAUGCCAAUACACUUAUCCCCCUACUCCCACAUCACACAGACGGUUCCACACACUCCUCACACGCUCUGGCCACACAGUAAACACACACAGACCACAGAGCUCAUGUCUGGGCUGCCCUGGUGCCCUCCUCUGGGCUCGUGCCCCCAGCCUCAGCAUUUACCCCCCAUUGAGGGCAGGGACCCACCCAGCUCCGUUUUCCUCCAUUUCAGCUCAGGGCCCUGCACCAAGUCUCUCCCAGUUGUUGCUUGGACCCGGACUCCUCCCACAGUCACCACUGUCACAGUCCCACCUCCUUCAAGGUCUCAAACACCCCUCCCCUGUUUCUGGCAGGAGCCGUCCUCACUCCCUCUAUUGCCUCUCCAGACCCAGACUUCACCCUCAGGUCACCCUCACCUGGACUUUGGGGUGCCCCACACCCCGCCCCAGGCCCUGGCCUCUGGAAUAUUUGGAAACUUGAACUGGGCCAGAGGCUUAAGCUCACAUCUGUCUGGAGCCUCAACUUUCUCCUCUGUAAAAUGGGCUAACACUGAAAGAACCUUGCAGAAUCUCAGCAACGUCACAGAGGACAUUGUUAGCACAGCCAGCGGGCUCCUGCUGGGCUGAGUUUGUGGGUAAUCCAAGCCUCGGCAGGUACAGUUCCUCCCUCAGGGCCCAGGACACAGUGAGCAUACAAUAGACAUUAGCUGCUGUGGUGUCUUGAUUUCAAGCCCAGUGCAGAUGCAUCUGACUUACGAAACUUCAGUGACACCUGCUCUGUGCCAGACACUGAAGAUGGAGCAGUGAACAGCACUGACCCAGCCUGUCCUCCUGUUGCCUGCAGGCCAGACGGAGUCUCACUCUGUCACCAGGCUGGAGUACAGUGGUGUGAUCUCGGCUCACUGCAACCUCCGCCUCCCAGGUUCAAGCGAUUCUCCUGCCUCAGCCUCUCAAGUAGCUGAGAUUACAGACGUGUGUCACCAUGCCCUGUUAAUUUUUGUUUGUUUGUUUUGUUUUUUGUUUUGUUUUGUUUCGUUUUUUGUUUUUUUUUUUUGAGACGGAGUCUUGCUCUGUCGCCCAGGCUGGAGUGCAGUGGCCCCGAUCUCGGCUCACCGCAAGCUCCGCCUCGCGGGUUCAUGCCAUUCUCCGGCCUCAGCCUCCCGAGUAGCUGGGACUACAGGCAUCCGCCACCACACCCAGCUAAUUUUUUGUAUUUUUUUUAGUAGAGACGGGGUUUCACUGUGUUAGCCAGGAUGGUCUCGAUCCCCUGACCUUGUGAUCCACCCAAGGCCUCGGCCUCCCAAAGUGCUGGGAUUACAGGCAUGAGCCACCGUGCCCGGUCAAUUUUUAUAUUUUUUGUAGAGACAGGGUUUCACCAUGUUGGCCAGGCUGGUGUCGAACUCCCGACCUCAGGUGAUUGUCGGCCUUGGCCUCCCAAAGUGCUGGGAUUACAGGCGUGAGCCACCGCGCCCAGCCGGUGGGCAGCCAGUUGUGUUCCGGGAGGAGGAGGACACCCUGGAAAGACAGUGGGGCCAGACACUGAACUGCCUUUGGAAGCAAGUAGGAGCAACAGCGAAGGUUUGCUGGCUCAGAAGCAAGGUCUCGCUGUGUUACCCUGGCUGGAGUGCAGUGGCUACUUACAGGCAUGAUCAUAGCAUACUGCAGCCUCGAACUCCUGGACUAGAGCAGUUCUCCUGCCUCAGCCUCCAGAGCAGCUGGGACUGCAGACACGCACCACAGAGCCCAGCCUGAGUCAUUUUGAUUCUGUAACUGGCUUCCUCUCGGCGGGCAGGCUCACACCCUCCACCCCCAGCUGGAGAUGGAAGGAGGAUGCUCACCGCCCAUUCCUCAUGCAGGCCAUCGAUGGAAAUGUCAGACAGUGCGAGUCCACGCCUGAACACUUCUGGGGUCCGCUCUGGGACUGACACUGGCAGAUCCAUCGGUGAGCUCCCGCCUGCCACCUCUGGGCCUGCAUUGCGGUGAUAGGGCCAAGGGCCUGGGCCUUCAAUUCUCCAGACUUGCCAAAAUGCUCAGCGCAGGCCUCGUCGGCAACUGCAGACAAGCAGAGGCAGCACCUGGGCUCUGCCUGUGCCUGGCACAGUGAAGCGAGGGUGGGGGCAGGAAUGAGGGUCCUCUCCAUGCAAGGGGGGAAGAUAGAAGAACAAAAUUUCACCCUAAUGUAGUGUCUUUAGACCGUGCAAUGUUGUGCUCCUGUUAGUCUGAUAUCAGGGGCUUGCAGCCUGGCAAAGGAAAAAAAACAGGCUGAGGCACAUGAUAGAAGACAGGCAGGGAUGCCACAAUCAUAACCAUGGCAAAGACCAGGAUCAGAAAGGCCCACCAUCUCUGACCCCAAAUCCCUGGGCAGAUGGUUCCAGAACUCAGAAUUUUCCCAGUUGUAGAAAGAUGGGGCCAGGUGCAGUGGCUCACGCCUGUAAUCCCAGCAUUUUGGGAGUACAAGGUGGGCGGAUCACCUGAGGUCAGGAGUUCGAGACCAGCCUGGCCAACAUGGUGAAACCCUGUCUCUACUAAAAAAAAAAAAAAAAAUUAGCCGGGCGUGGCGAUGCAUGCCUGUAAUCCCAGCUACUCGGGAGGCUGAGCCAGGAGAAUUGCUUGAACCCGGGAGGCGGAGGUUGCAGUGAGCCAAGAUCGCGCCACUACACUCCAGUCCGGGCGACAGAGCAAGAGUCCAUUCCCCCACCACCAAAAAAAAAAAAAAAAGAAAGAAAGAUGAUGUGAUACAUAUCACAUAUUUCCUAACACCCCCAACCAAACACAUUUAUGCAUAUGCAUAAAGCAGACGAGGAAAGAUUCUAAAUAGGCUCUGAAUCUCAGUUUUCUCAUCUCUACAAUGGGGCAGUGAUGGCAUGCACCUCCCAGGGCUGUUCUGAGAAUCUGAUGCCUCCCAUUGCACUGGUGAGCCUGGCACAGGCACAGGUCCCACCCCAGGCCCUUUGAACUGGCUGUUCCUUUGGCCUGGAACAUUCCUCCCCAGAUACCUCCUGAGAGGGCUCCCUCACUUCCUUCAAGGCACUGCUCAAAUGCUACCUCUUCACAGAGGCUUUCCCUGACCACCCCGUCUCUUUCCUCUUCCUGCAUAGCCUCUGUCACCUGACAUUUUAUGUCAUAAAUUACUCAUUUAUUAAUUUCCUGCUCUCCCACAGUGGCACCCGAGCUCUGUGAGGGCAAGACUUUGUUCGGUUGUGGGCUAUGCCCCCAACCCCUCGGACAGUGCCUGCACAGGUGGACAUUUUUGUUGGAUGAAGGAUUUUCUGUUAAAUGUGUCUGGCACACACAGAAAAACAAAGCCCAGCAGGUACGAUGGUGAUUAUUAUUGUUACUGGUGGCGCUCUAUUAUUGUUAUUAGUGUCUGUUGAAAAAGACCCUGAGCUAUACCAGCCCUUGGUUCUCCAGCCUGUGAAAUGGGCAUCCUGGGCACUGAGGCACUAGCCUUGGGAAGCUGAUAGGGGGUCCCUGCAGGAGAGACAAAGAACACUGCCCACCCCCCCGGGGGAGCCUGCGCCCCUCACCGGAAAGAGAAGCAGGGGGGAGCAGAGGGAGCUUGCAGCCCCACACGCAGGGCUGCCAGAAGGCCAUACAUAAUUCAUUGCCAAAUGGGGCUGCGGGCGGCUCUCCGCGGCGUGCGCUGGGGGCUCACUCUGCGCCUGGCACUUCGCUGACUGCGCCUCACACGUUGCCUCAUUGCAUCUUCAUGGAUUUGCAGGGUGUGACCCUUCCCCCUGUUUUACCCAGGGGGAUCCUGAGGCUCAGAGGAUGGGGCCACCGUGCUAGUCACACAGCCUCUCUGUGGCCAAGCUGGGCCUCGGGCCAGCAGAUUCGGCCCCCAGCGGCCCCCAUUCACUGCCUCUCUGCUGAGGGAAAAGACGGGCCUGGGGAGCGGGUGGGAGGCACAAAGGAGACCCCGCUCUGAGACAGGCUGCAGAAGAGGGAGCUGGGUCUCAGCAGGGCUGGGGAAGGCUCUGGCCCCAGCCCUCCGCCCAACCCCCUGCCCUCCUCUCCUGGAGGAGAUGCUCCCCAAAUUAGCCAUCAUGAGCGCUGGCUCUGGGGGUUGGGCGUUGGGGAGCAGUUUGCUCAGCUGUAAAAUGGGAAUAACAGAAGCCGUCCCUGGGACUAUGAGAUCAAGGUGCUCAAGAAAAGUGGUGUCUGCUGAGGGGAAAAGCCAGUCCCAAAAGGUUGCAUACUCUCAUUCUGUUUAUUUGUUUUUGUUUUUGAGACAGGGUCUCGCCCUGUCACCCAGGCUGGAGUACAGUGGCGCAAUAUGGGCUCACUGCAACCUCCACCUCCUGGGCUCAAGUGAUCCUCCCAUCUCAGACCCUCAAGGAGCUGGGGCUACAGGCACGUGCCACCGUGUCCGGCUAAUUUUUGUAUUUUUUGUAGAGACAGGGUUUCACCAUGUUGCCCAGGCUGGUCUCAAACUCCUGAGCUCAGGUGAUCCGCCUGCCUUGGCCUGCGAUAAAAUUGCACAGAAGUAAAUACACACACGUGAGGAUACGGAAAACCGGGGAAACCUGAGCAAGAGCAGUCAGACCCCGGCUGUGAUGGCGCCCAGUAGUUCUGCGAGAUGUUACCAUUGGGGAAACUGAGUGAAGGCGGGUACCUGGGAUCCCUCUGUUUUCUUUUUUGUUGUUGUUGUUAUUUUGAGAUGAAGUUUCCCUCUUGUUGCCCAGGCUGGGUGAUCCACCUGCCUCGGCCUCCCAAAGUGCUGGGAUUACACGCGUGAGCCACUGUGCCCAGCCUCUCUGUUUUAUUUCUUCUUUUUUUUUUUUUUUUUUUGGAGACGCUCUGUCGCCCAGGCUGGAGUGCAGUGGCACGAUAUUGGCUCACUGCAAGCUCCGCCUCCUGGGUUCACACCAUUCUCCUGCCUCAGCCUCCCGAGUAGCUGGGACUACAGGCGCCCGCCACCUCGCCCGUCUAAUUUUUUGUAUUUUUAGUAGAGGCGGGGCUUCACCGUGUUAGCCAGGAUGGUCUCAAUCUCCUGACCUCGUCAUCCGCCCGUCUCGGCCUCCCAUAGUGCUGGGAUUACAGGCAUGAGCCACCACGCCCGGCUGUUUUAUUUCUUAUAACUGUACAGGAAUCUACAAUGAUUGUAACAAAAAUUUCAAUUAAGGCCACUCUAGGCACAUGGCCUGUGGGGUAGCCCUGCUCAACAAGAAGCCGUCAAAAAAAUGUUUUUUAAUUAAAAAAUUUCUUCAAUUAAAAAGCGUUAUCUUCCUCUGCCCGGAAAGGGUUAAGUGAGUCACUGCAGUUAGCUCCCCUUCCCCCACAACCACCUAGACCAGGCCAGGGACCAGCGGGCAAUUGCCUGGCAGCUGGAGUUUUCCUCCACUGUGGACUGUACUUCUUGCGUCACUCUGAAUGUCUCCAGUCUUUAUUCCAGAAUGUUCUGGUCCUCUCCCACUUUUCCAAGGACAGGAAUUCCCUAGUGGGGCUCCAGAAGAGGCUCUGGAGGAGAACAAGAAAGGCCCUUGUCAUCCAUUGGCCUCAGGCUGGGAAAUCUCGGUUCCACUCCCAGCCCAGCCUCAAUAUUAGGUUGUCAGUCUGGAGUCUGAGAGCCAUGCCCCCACCCCCUUAGUCCUUCACCUCCAGGAGAGUUGGGGAUACUGGAAAGAAUGUUGAGUGUCAGAGCCCCUCUCAGUGGCUCACGCCUGAAAUCCCAGCCCUUUGGGAGGCUGAGGCAGGUGGAUUGCUUGAGGCCAAGAGUUCAAGACCAGCCUGGCCAACGCGACGAAACCCUGACUCUACUAAAAAUACAAAAAUUAGCUGGGCGUGGUGGCACACACCUGUAAUCCCAGCAGCUCGGGAGGCUGAGGCAGGAGAAUUGUUUGAACCUGAGAGGUGGAGGUUGCAGUGAGCUGAGAUCACAACACUGCACUCAAAAAGUAGUUAAUUAAUUUAGUUUAAUUAAAAAAGAAUAUUGAGUGUCAGGCAAUCUGGGUAGAACCCAUUGUGUUUCUACAGGAUAGAAUCUGCUGUGUUCUCUAGCGGAACUUCCGGAUCACCUUCACCGUAUGACUCUAGACAAUCCCUGUCCACUCUUCAGUUUUAGAUGCCCCAUUCAAAGAAUGAAAGAAUUGUCCUAGAUGAUCCUUUAGGGUCUUCCAGGCUGAUGACAAGGGGGACCUGGCCCCUCUGCUGCUGGCCAAAGAGGACUUUACUUCCCAUUCCGUGUGGUUGAACAAGAAUUGCUGGGCUCCAGUCCUGCCUUUGGCCCUUCCCUACAUGUGACCUUGGGCCCUCUUUGCCUUUCAGAAUCAAUACAGUGAGAGAGUUAACACAAGCUCAGGUUAGUAAGUCAUUCAACAAACAUUUACUGAGCGCUUAUCAAAUACUGCAUGCUGGAGUGGACACUGGAGAAAAAGGUGAGGAGAAGGCCGGGCGCAGUGGCUCGUGACUGUAAUUCCAGCACUUUGAGGGGCAGAGGCAGGUGGAUUACCUGAGGUCAGGAGUUUGAGACCAGCCUGGCCAACAUGGCAAAACCCCGUCUCUACUAAAAAUACAAAUAUUAGCCAGGCAUGGUGGUGCAUAUCUGUAGUCCCAGCUACUCAGGAGGCUGAGCAGGAGAAUCACUUGAACUCAGGAGGUGGAGCGUGCAGUGGGCCGAGAUUGCACCUCUGCACUCCAGCCUGGGCAACAUAGUGAGACUCUGUCUCAAAUAAAUAAAUAAAGUGAGGAGAAAAAAAUACCAUCUCUGUCUUCACAGAACUUAUAGUUUGAGAGGGGAGAAUCCCACAAGUAAAUUAUAAAUCUCAGCUGAGAUUAUGCAAAGAAGCAAAGGCCGGACGUGGUGGCUCACGCCUGUAAUCCCAGCACUUUGGGAGGCCGAGACGGGCGGAUCAUGAGGUCAGGAGAUUGAGACCAUCCUGGCUAACACGGUGAAACCCUGUCUCUACUAAAAAUACAAAAAAAUUAGCUGGGCGUGGUGGCGGGCGUCUGUAGUUCCAGCUACUCGGGAGGCUGAGGCAGGAGGAUGGCGUGAACCCAGGAGCACAGGUUGCAGUGAGCCGAGAUGGCGCCACUGCACUCCAGCCUGGGCGACAGAGCGAGACUCUGUCUCAAAAAAAAAAAAAAAAAAGGAAGCAAAGUGCCCAGCUGGGAUGGUGGUUUCAGAGGCCACAGUGGGAGCUUCCCAGAGAAGGGAUGAUUGAGCUAAGUCUAAGCAAAAGGGGUGGUCAGGGCAGCAGCUGCUCCAAAACAGGGGCUGGGGGCUUAUGUGGAGAGAGAAGACAUGGAGAGACCAUGCCCAGAAGGAGGCGGCGGCUUCAGUGAACAGUGCAGGGGAGCAGGUCCGAGGAGGCCGCCUACCAGGGGAAGGAGUCUCAUCUCCAUCCUAGACAAAAAAAGGAUCUUUUGAGAUGCAUUAAGCAGGGGAGUCACAGAUUGGAUUUGUGUUUUGAGAAUCUCCUGCUUACCUAGAGAAGAAGGGCAUCUCCUGGGCCCUCACUGUUGCCUUAAAUGAUUUUUAUUGUGUAUUACUUAAACAUGUGCAAGCAUAAAAUGAGAUAUAAACUCCUUGUAGCUCUUAUACAAGCAUCAGACCAAGACAAAUUGACCCAUCACGUACAAAAUCGAUUCAAAUCAGAUUAAUUUUAUGUGACAUGUUAUUAUGCCUUUUGUCUGAAACCCUGCCACCACCCACAGUGCAAUUAUGGCCCAACCACUGUGGUGUUCUGAAUUUGUGGGACAGAGAAUAUUGGCCUUUUAAACACGUGCAUGCAUGCAUUUGCGUGUGCGCACACACACACAUCCCAAAUGAUUUUUUCCCACUAUAUAUGAAGAACUCCUACAAACCAAAAAGAAAAAGGCAGACAAUUCAAGAGAAAAAUGGGGGAGGGCUUGCAUUAAAGUACUUCAUAACAAGAGUACUUAGGAGGCCAACAAAUACACGAAAAGCUGCUAGCUUCAUGACUCAUGGGGGUGGCUUGGUCAGUUCAGGAUACUGUAACAAAAUACCUUAGACUGGGAAAUUUAUAAACAACGGAAUUUAUUGCUCACAGUUCUGGAGGCUGGGAAGUCCAAGAUCAAGGCAGCAGUAGAUCCGGUGCCUGAGCCCGUUCCCUGCUUCAAACAUGGCACCUUCUUGCUGUAUCCUCACAUGGUGGAAGGGGGAAGACAGUUCUCUGGGGCCUCUUUUAUAAGGGCAGUUAUCCAAUUCACAAGGAUAGAGCCCUCAUGACCUAAUCACCUUUCAAAGAUCCCCAUCUUCUAACACCUUCUAACACCAUCACCUUGGUGAUUAGGUCUUUUUGUUGUUGUUGUUGUUGAGAUGGACUCUCACUCUGUUGCCUAGGCUGGAGUGCAGUGGCGUAAUCUUGGUUCACUGCAACCUCUGCCUCCCGGGCUGAAGUGAUUAUCCUGUCUCAGCCUCCCAAGUGGCUGGGAUUACAGGCGUGUGCCACCAUGCCCGGCUAAUUUUCAUAUUUUUAGUAGAGACAGGGUUUCACCAUGUUGGUCAGGCUGGUCUCGAACUCCUGACCUCAUGAUCCGCCCACUUCGUCCUCCCAAAAUGCUGGGAUUACAGGCAUGAGCCACUGCACCCAGCCGAUUAAGUCUUAACGUAUGAGUUUUUGGGAGAAACUCAAACAUUCGGACAAUAGCAAGGAGAAUACAAAACCACAGUGAGCUACCGCUUCAGACACCAGAGAAGUUUAAGUGAAAAAGACUGGCAAUACCAAGUGCUGAUGAGGAUAUGGAGCAACCAGAACUCUCAGACAUUGCUGAUGGGAAUCUAAAUUAGUAUAACCACCACGAAAGCAUCCGUAAGGUUUAAUUGUGUUGAACACACCCUGCCCUCUGACCAAGCAUUUCCACUCCUGGGCAUACAGGCAAAAGAAAUGCAUCCACGUGUUCAUCAAAAGAUGUAACCUGUGCCAGGUGAGGUGGUUCAUGCCUGUAAUCCCAGCACAUCGGGAGGCCAAGGAGGGAGGAUUGCUUGAGCCCAGAAGUUCGAGAGCAGCCUAGGCAACAAGGCAAAACCUCGUCUCUACUAAAAAGUAGCCAGGCAUGAUGGUAUAUGCCUGUAGUCCCAGCUACUCAGGAGGCCAAGGCAUGCAGAUUGAUUGAACCCGGAAGGUGGAGGCUACAGUGAAUUGUGAUCUCGCCACUGCACUCCAGCCUGGGUGACAGAGCAAGAUCUUGUCUCAAUUAAAAAAAAAGGAAGAAAGAAAGACAUAACCUGGAAUAUUCACACCAACACUAUUCAGGAUAGCCCUAAACUGGAAAGAAUCUGAAUAUCCUCCGGCUUUAGAACAGAGAGAAAUUAUAGACUAUUCAUUCAUACAGGGGAUGAUUGAUCAGCUUUAAGAAUAAACAAACCGUACACAACAAUAUAGAUGAAUCUACAACCUUAAUGUGCAAAAUAGUUCACAUAUAUAAAGGACAAAAACAGGCAAAACUACUCCAUGGUGUUAGAAAUAGGGGUAGAGGUUACCCUCAUGCGGCAGGAGGGUUAGUGAUAGGGGAUUUGGAAGAGGAGGAGCCCAAUGGACUGAACAGCUGAGCUGGAAACAGCAAUUUGUUCCUUAAAGUUCUGAACCCAACUGUUAUCCAGCAUGGAGUCUGUCUGGAGAGGCCAGAUGUGGGGCCUCUCACAGGGGAAUGAGAAGUGCCUCUCAGGGUCCCACCCAUGAUCCCCCUUUCCUUGCCCACACAACCACCAACUGGCAAGUAGUAACCCAGGACCUGUAGCCCCCACUGGCUUGACACAGAGCAUAAUGCAAGCUUUUCCUGCUCCAGGUCCUGGACACCACUUUGCCCUUUGCCCCACACGUACAGCCCCCUGACCAAAAGCUGGGUACUCUGGCUUGACUAGAGGGAGCUAGACUCCAGGAAUAAGUAAGGAGCUGGGCUUCCACGCUAGAGAACAAGAGCUUCUCUGGGGAAAGGGGCUUCCCAUGAAGCCCUGGGGCACUGGGAGAUUAAUGGGCAGACCUCUGGCCUCAGCUUCCAGGGAAGGGGAGGGUGUGGGCCAACAUGCGGUGGCUACACUGACCACAAGCCGAUGACCCCAGCCAGCCUCAGGAUGUCUCAGCUCUAGGCAUGGUUUUUCGUUUUGUUUUGUCGUGUUUUGUUUUUGAGAUGGAACCUCGCUCUGUCGCCUAGGCUGGAGUGAAGUGGCACCAUCUCGUCUCCCUGCAACCUCCACCUCCUGGGUUCAAGCGAUUCUCCUGCCUCAGCCUCCUGAGUAGCUGAGAUUACAUGUGCGUGCCACCUUGCCCAGCUAAUUUUUGUAUUUUUAGUAGAGAUAGGGUUUCAUCAUGUUAGCUAGGCUGGUCUCAAACUCCUGACCUCAAGUGAUCUGCCUGCCUCAGCCUCCCAAAGUGCAAGGAUUACAGGCAUGAGCCACCAUGCCCGGCAUAGGCAUGGUUUUGACAAUCUGUCUCUUUGUGCCCUGGCUCCUUCUCCAACUCCUCUUUGGAGGAGGCACAGGAGGAGGGGUCAUUUCACUGUUCCUGAAAAGUAGACAUAUAACCUACAUGCAACUGCCAGGUGAUAAGGGCCCCAUCUGUCUGGCAUGACGUUGGAGGUCCACAAAGGCUGAUUAGAUGAAUGCUCAGCUCUGGGGCCUCCCCACAGAGCUCACAGACAGGCGUGAAGGAAAGCAGGACUCUUAUUAGAAUAUGUUCAGAGUUUUCACUGAAGAAGCCUCCUGUGUGGGCCAGGCACUGUGCUCAGUGCUUUGAUUCACAGUCUCAUUUAAUUCUCACCAUUUACAGACAAGAAUUCAGCUAAGAUCCUUUUCAAUCAAGUCUGGCAAUAUCUGCCUUUCAAUGGCAGUGCCUAGUCCUUUCAUAUGUAAUAUACUUAUCAUUAUGGGUGGGUUUAAGUUUUAUCAUCUUGCUAUUUGUUAUCUAUUUGUCCCCCCUCUUUUGUUCCUCCUUUACUGCCUUCUAUUUGGUUGAGACUUAAUAAAAUAUUUUAUUCCA